AGACAGACCACAUGUUUCCUAUCUUGGAAAAUGGUACCACUUCCUUGUGCAAGCCUACCCCUGUUCCCUCACCCCUCGUUCAGUCCAACAGCAAAUCUGUCCAGUCUUCUAACUGUAUCUCAGGUUCAUUAGCCCCGCUUCCUCGUCCCUGCUCGUCUUCUGCCGGACCAGUCCGCCAUCUUGUGACCGGACUCGGGAAUAGCGUCCUACUUCCCGGCGGCCUCCACUCUUGACCCAAAUGCAAUGUGCAGCCAUGGCAAUCUUUUAUAAACAGAAAUCCGAUCAAGUUACUCCUCUGCCGAAAUCCCUCUGGUCAGUGGUUUAACUGUCGAGGUGCUCCUGGCAGCACUCUGCCCUCCCCACAUCAUUGCUGGUGGACUUGUCUCCCCUACUAGACUGUGCCCUGUGAGGGUGGAGACUUUGUGCAGGGUUGUAUCCCCAGCAUCUGAUGCAGUGAUUCAAUAAACAUCUGUCCAAUUAAUAGGAAAGACAGUUCCUUUUCUCAUUCCCCUAUUGCUGGUCCCCUGCCCUCAAGCAGGAUGUUAUGCCCCAGAGUGGCUGUGGGUGCGAACAUUCUGCCCCUCUGGCUGGUCUGGCACUGAUUUCCACCCUGAGCUGGUGUUGCCUCUCUCCUUCCUCUUGGCCAACCUCUCUUCCACCAAUAUAAGCCCAAACUGGAGGCCAGCAGGCAGUCAUGCGUUUUAUGGCAGGCCCUGCAGGGAGCCAGAGUCUGGGUCCCCUGUGCUUCCACAGCAGCCCCCAAGCCCUCUACACGGUCCUCUUAAUAGUGCUGGUCAUGAUGAGCUUGGUGUUUGGUAAGUUUGUUCCUGUCAAUUGGGAACCCCCUCAACCACUUCCAUUCCCCAAAUACCUGCGCUGCUACCGAUGCCUCUUGGAGACCAAGGAGUUAGGGUGCCUUCUGGGAUCUGACAUCUGCCUCACCCCAGCUGGCAGCAGCUGCAUCACUCUCCACAAAAAGAACAGCAGCGGUUCUGACGUCAUGGUGAGUGACUGCCGAAGUAAGGAGCAGAUGAGUGAUUGUUCAAAUACCCGAACUUCUCCGGUGUCUGGCUUCUGGAUAUUCUCUCAAUACUGCUUCCUGGAUUUCUGCAAUGACCCUCAAAACAGAGGGCUCUAUACUCCUUAGUGUGACUGCAGCAAACUUUGGUGUAAAAUUCCACCAGUUUCCAGCCACCUUCCUGACUUCUAUCUGGGCUUGGCCAGGACUUCUAGUCCCUCAUACCAGCCCUCCUUGCCUCCCUCCAGCCACUGGACCCCAGCCUUGGCUCUUCCUCUUGGUUGACGCCCUUCAGCACACUUACUGCUACUCUGUACCCCCAGCCCUACUGCCCACCAGGUUUCCUCUCUUGUCCCCUAGUCCCUGGAUGUUUCUCCCAAAUAAAUUUGUGUGUAAACUGUU